AUGUUAAAGAUGAGCGGGUGGCAGCGACAGAGCCAAAAUCAGAGCUGGAACCUGAGGAGAGAGUGUUCAAGAAGGAAGUGUAUCUUCAUACAUCACCACACCUGA